GGGAGCUGGUGGAGGUGGCCUGGCCAACCGGGCUGCAGGGUGCACAACCUGGUGGGGUGUGUAGGCCGGGCAUUCAGGGCUCAGCCCCAGUUGGAAAUUGGUCUAGGUGACCUUGAAAUCCCUUCCAGUCUGAGGUCUUUGACAGGGACCCAAGGUUCUGAUUAUCAGACUCAGUGGCCCCUUGGGCUCCCGGCCCUGGGCAAUUCUCAGCCCUCGAGAUGGCCCAGCUGAGAGUCCCUGUGUCCCUGUCCCACUUCCACAUCCCACCACGCAGGACCGCUUGGUAAACUUCCCCUUCUCUACUUUCCAUUACAAAGGUUUGAGGGGUUUGUUUUUUUUUUAACCAUCUGAAUAUUAAAUUAUCACAAAGUUUGAGGCCCCCAACCUCCCUUGGGUUCAGUAAUUCACUAGAAGGACUCAUAGAAUCCACUGAAGUGGAUACACUCACAGGUACCGUUUAUUACAGCAAAGGAUGCAGGCUUAAGUCUGCAGAGGGACCAGGCACAAGCUUCCCCUUGUCCUCUCCCUGUGGGGUCAUGUGGACAGUCCUUAAUUCUCCCAGAAUGACGUGUGACGAGACGUGGGAAGUACUGCCAACUUGGGAAGCUCUACGAGCCCCGGUGUCCAGAGGUUUUAUCAGGGCUCAAUCACAUAGACCCAGCUGACCACCCGCAUGGCUGACCUCAGUCUCAGCCCCUCCAGAGGCUACGCCGAUAGUGCGGCCCAAGGCCCCACCAUACAUCACAUUGUCAGCUAGACCAUCCAGCAUGGCUCAAGGCCCAGAAGAGAGCCCAGCAAGCUGGAGGAGGCUGAAGAGAGAGGCUUCCUGCUGGUCAUCUGGGUCCAGAAUGCCUGGAGAUCUCUGCUCAGCCCUGGUGCCCAGCAGCCCUGACAAGGAUGACCAGCUGAUCUGUGUGAACGAGAACGGCGGCUGUGAGCAGUACUGCAGUGACCACACGGGCACCAAGCGCUCCUGUCGGUGCCACGAGGGGUACUCUCUGCUGGCAGACGGGGUGUCCUGCACACCCACAGUUGAAUAUCCAUGUGGAAAAAUACCUAUUCUAGAAAAAAGAAAUGCCAGCAAACCCCAAGGCCGAAUUGUGGGGGGCAAGGUGUGCCCCAAAGGGGAGUGUCCAUGGCAGGUCCUGUUGUUGGUGAAUGGAGCUCAGUUGUGUGGGGGGACCCUGAUCAACACCAUCUGGGUGGUCUCCGCGGCCCACUGUUUCGACAAAAUCAAGAACUGGAGGAACCUGAUCGCGGUGCUGGGCGAGCACGACCUCAGCGAGCACGACGGGGAUGAGCAGAGCCGGCGGGUGGCGCAGGUCAUCAUCCCCAGCACGUACGUCCCGGGCACCACCAACCACGACAUCGCGCUGCUCCGCCUGCACCAGCCCGUGGUCCUCACUGACCAUGUGGUGCCCCUCUGCCUGCCCGAACGGACGUUCUCUGAGAGGACGCUGGCCUUCGUGCGCUUCUCAUUGGUCAGCGGCUGGGGCCAGCUGCUGGACCGUGGCGCCACGGCCCUGGAGCUCAUGGUCCUCAACGUGCCCCGGCUGAUGACCCAGGACUGCCUGCAGCAGUCACGGAAGGUGGGAGACUCCCCAAAUAUCACGGAGUACAUGUUCUGUGCCGGCUACUCGGAUGGCAGCAAGGACUCCUGCAAGGGGGACAGUGGAGGCCCACAUGCCACCCACUACCGGGGCACGUGGUACCUGACGGGCAUCGUCAGCUGGGGCCAGGGCUGCGCAACCGUGGGCCACUUUGGGGUGUACACCAGGGUCUCCCAGUACAUCGAGUGGCUGCAAAAGCUCAUGCGCUCAGAGCCACGCCCAGGAGUCCUCCUGCGAGCCCCAUUUCCCUAGCCCAGCAGCCCUGGCCUGUGGAGAGAAAGCCAAGGCUGCGUCGAACUGUCCUGGCACCAAAUCCCAUAUAUUCUUCUGCAGUUAAUGGGGUAGAGGAGGGCAUGGGAGGGAGGGAGAGGUGGGGAGGGAGACAGAGACAGAAACAGAGAGAGACAGAGACAGAGAGAGACUGAGGGAGAGACUCUGAGGACAUGGAGAGAGACUCAAAGAGACUCCAAGAUUCAAAGAGACUAAUAGAGACACAGAGAUGGAAUAGAAAAGAUGAGAGGCAGAGGCAGACAGGCGCUGGACAGAGGGGCAGGGGAGUGCCAAGGUUGUCCUGGAGGCAGACAGCCCAGCUGAGCCUCCUUACCUCCCUUCAGCCAAGCCCACCUGCACGUGAUCUGCUGGCCUCAGGCUGCUGCUCUGCCUUCAUUGCUGGAGACAGUAGAGGCAUGAACACACAUGGAUGCACACACACACACGCCAAUGCACACACACAGAGAUAUGCACACACACGGAUGCACACACAGAUGGUCACACAGAGAUACGCAAACACACCGAUGCACACGCACAUAGAGAUAUGCACACACAGAUGCACACACAGAUAUACACAUGGAUGCACGCACAUGCCAAUGCACGCACACAUCAGUGCACACGGAUGCACAGAGAUAUGCACACACCGAUGUGCGCACACACAGAUAUGCACACACAUGGAUGAGCACACACACACCAAUGCGCACACACACCGAUGUACACACACAGAUGCACACACAGAUGCACACACACCGAUGCUGACUCCAUGUGUGCUGUCCUCUGAAGGCGGUUGUUUAGCUCUCACUUUUCUGGUUCUUAUCCAUUAUCAUCUUCACUUCAGACAAUUCAGAAGCAUCACCAUGCAUGGUGGCGAAUGCCCCCAAACUCUCCCCCAAAUGUAUUUCUCCCUUCGCUGGGUGCCGGGCUGCACAGACUAUUCCCCACCUGCUUCCCAGCUUCACAAUAAACGGCUGCGUCUCCUCCGCACACCUGUGGUGCCUGCCACCCACUGGGUUGCCCAUGAUUCAUUUUUGGAGCCCCCGGUGCUCAUCCUCUGAGAUGCUCUUUUCUUUCACAAUUUUCAACAUCACUGAAAUGAACCCUCACAUGGAAGCUAUUUUUUAAAAACAAAAGCUGUUUGAUAGAUGUUUGAGGCUGUAGCUCCCAGGAUCCUGUGGAAUUGGAUGUUCUCUCCCUGCCACAGCCCUUGUCAAUGAUAUUUCACAGAGACCCUGGGAGCACCUGCUCAAGAGUCAGGGACACACGCAUCACUAAAUGCAAGUUCCCAGGCCCUGGCUGCAGUGGGAGGACCUGGCAAGCUGCACUCUUGCUGAGUCCCCAGGGUGGUGGAAGAAGAAUGAGAAACACAUGAACAGAGAAAUGGGGAGGUGACAAACAGUGCCCCCACUCAGACUCCGGCAAGCACGGCUCAGAGAGUGGACUCGAUGCCAUCCCUGCAGGGCCGUCCUGGGCACCACUGGCACUCACAGCAGCAAGGUGGGCACCAUUGGCACUCACAGCAGCAAGGCAGGCACCAGCAACCCACCUCGGGGGCACUCAGGCAUCAUCUACUUCAGAGCAGACAGGGUCUAUGAACUACAGCCGUGGGCUGCUUCCAAGGCACCCUGCUCUUGUAAAUAAAGUUUUAUGGGAACACACCCA